AUGCCGUAUACUCUCAACAGGUUUUCUCAUUUGCUCCUUGGGACAGCUCGGUAAGGAUGAUACAGUCAGUUCUAUCUCACAGAUAAUCAAGCUCAGGCUUUCAGAGCCUAAGUCACCUUCCCAGAAGAACAGGCCCGGCACCACCUCUGCGCACAACCCCGCGGGCCUGGCUCAGGCGGGAGUGCGGGGCCAGCACCAUGAGCGCCCCGGGCAGCCCCGACCAGGCCUAUGACUUCCUGCUCAAGUUCCUGCUGGUGGGCGACAGGGACGUAGGCAAGAGUGAGAUCCUGGAGAGCCUGCAGGAUGGUGCAGCUGAGUCCCCGUACAGCCAUCUCGGGGGGAUCGACUACAAGACGACCACCAUCCUGCUGGACGGCCAGCGGGUGAAGCUGAAGCUCUGGGAUACGUCGGGGCAGGGAAGAUUUUGUACCAUAUUCCGCUCCUACUCUCGUGGUGCACAAGGAGUGAUCCUGGUCUACGACAUUGCAAACCGCUGGUCUUUCGAGGGUAUGGAUCGAUGGAUUAAGAAGAUUGAGGAACAUGCCCCUGGUGUCCCUAAAAUCCUGGUGGGGAAUCGCCUACAUCUGGCAUUCAAGAGGCAGGUGCCCAGGGAGCAGGCCCAGGCCUACGCCGAGCGCCUGGGUGUGACCUUCUUUGAGGUCAGCCCUCUGUGCAAUUUCAACAUCAUAGAGUCUUUCACGGAGCUGGCCAGGAUAGUGCUGCUGCGGCACAGGAUGAAUUGGCUCGGGAGGCCGAGCAAGGUACUGAGCUUGCAAGACCUCUGCUGCCGCACCAUCGUGUCCUGCACACCUGUGCAUCUGGUGGACAAGCUCCCGCUCCCCAGUACCUUAAGAAGCCACCUCAAGUCCUUCUCCAUGGCUAAGGGCCUGAAUGCCAGGAUGAUGCGAGGCCUCUCCUACUCCCUCACCACCAGCUCCACUCACAAGAGCAGCCUCUGCAAAGUGGAGAUCGUCUGCCCACCCCAGAGCCCACCCAAAAACUGCACCAGAAACAGCUGCAAAAUUUCUUAAGGAAGGCACCAAAAGGAAACAAGCUGGAAUCGCUCCAGGAAAAACUCUGGUUACACCUGGAAGAUGGAAGUCGCAUUGUAGAUUCAAGAAAUUAGUUUUCAGUUUCUCACGGGAACCAUGCUGCUUGGGAAUGUGUGUGAUGCCUUCUGUCAAUAAAAACACAUUACACAGUUUGACUUUGAAUUUCUAUUUGGAUGUGCAUGAAGCUCUUGUUUUAAACGUGUGUUUAUAAAGGGGAAAUUAGUACUUUGCUCAACUCUUGAUAACGUGAAAUUUUGAAUGUUACUUAUAUCAUAAUCACGCUGCAACUUUUUCCUUAAAAUAACCGCCUUUGUUAGAAUGGUGAUAUGGCAAUGAUGAGUAUAAAUUCAAGGAAAUUUGAGAAGCAAUGAUAGUGAGAUAAUUCAGUCAUCGAUAGUACAAGAGGGGCCUUUUUGUAAACCUCCUUUUUAAUGUCAAAGCACCAAUUUAUAAAACACUGCAGAUGCAUAUAGAGAUUGUAUAUAACAGAUCUGUCCAGCUUGUGCAUGAAAUGGAUUUGAUAAAGUUUUUGCUAUGUUAUUUACUACAUUUGGGGAUUAAUACGUGAUUUAUAUGUAUGUUUUUCUGUAAAUCUACUUUUUUUGUACGAGAUGUUCUACAAGAUAUGAAGCUAAGGGAGGAAAACACCAAAGAUAUCUCUAGUUAUGUUGAACAUAGCCAAUAUGGUUUCAAUGGAUCAAUAAGAAAAAACCAUUUCAGUAAGGAAUGAAAUACGUACUUAUUUGAGAAAAUGUUUCUUAACAGUAAAAAAGUAUAUAUUUUUCUCUUUGGUAAAACGAAAAGAGAGGAAAAAUAUGUAUAGUGUAACCCCGCAAGAUGAGGCUUUGCAGAAAAACAAUGCAAUAGAACAUGGCGGGGCAGGCCCAUUAUAAGGCCUUAGGUGAGUCAUUUCCCCUGUGCUGGCCAGUUUUGGUUAACACCUCUCAGAUCAAUAUAGAGGUUAAUGAGAUCACAUCUGGGAAAGCACUUCUGAGACCUUAGAUGGGAAAGAAGGAGAAGUGGUUUCCACGUAGUUACUUUCCAAUUUACACUGUUGAUUAUUAUAAUAAUUGAUAUUGGAUGAACUGAGUAAAUAUAAGUCCUUGUACUCUUUUGUAAUUGAAUGACCAUUUAUUUGUGCAUUGUCAUAGGGUGAUUGUAACAAAGUCCCGCAGAAGGGCAGUAUCUCUGGCCUCACGGAGCUGUGGGGACUCACCCUUCCUGAACGCUGGUACUUUUCUAUCUCAUGAAUUUCCCACAACAUUCCUGGGAGGUAGAGGAUAUAAUCUCUACACCAUCCUGUAGCUUAAGAAACAGGGAUGUUUGCAGGUUAAGCAACCUGGCUGGGGAGCAUCCUGCCACUAAGUGGAAAAGCAGAGACUAGCAUCCUAUAUGCCCCCAGGCAGACUGUGAUGCUGAGCUGCACAUCACAACAUAACCAAGCAAAUCUUGCUUUCCUGCUGACCUGGGUCACUACUGAAAUCUGUAUCUUCAGCUCUGAAGCCAGGCUGCCAGUUCUGUCUCUCUUAUGAAAGACAGAGAACCUUGUCAGACCUAAAUUUCCUACUCUGUAGACAAGGGAGUGUGUCUGGGCCAUUGCUUUAGAAACGAGUCCGCAGACAGUUCCUGUAUCAGGAAGAAUAUGCACUCUCAGAGGGACAGGGGCCAUGCUGAGGGUGAAUACUUGAAGGAGCAGGCCCCAAACACAUGCAGAUCGGGGAUGCAUAGAGUCUUUAAUAGAAAUUACCAAAUCAACCUUGAAAGAGGUUGUACUAAAUGACAUCCCCACCACCAAUAUGAAACAGGGUAGGCUUCCCCGCAUGCCCACCUUACUGGAAUCCUGAAUGGUUUCUUUUUAUACUUUGAUGAUAUGACAGGUGGAAAUUCUUUCAUUGUCAUUAUAUUUAAUUUGAUGUUCAGAUAACUUAAAAAAUUCCCUAGUAUACAAAAUGCUCUGAUAAUCAUCAUUGCAUUAUAUUUUUAUUGCAAACUGGUCCAUUUUCAUAUGUAGCCUAAAAACAAUGAGCAACAGGCACAUUAGCCUGCAAGUUCUCCUAGAGCUACUGGUGGCAUUAUGGUUCCAGGGUGUGUUUGUGGCCUCUGGGGAAUACUGAUGGCAGUGUGUUUGUCUAGAAGAUUAAGAACAUCUCUCUGUGAUAUUAGUUGAAUUCAAUAUUAGAGAAGAGCUGGAGUCUUUUUAAGUGACACAAGAGCUGGACCACAACAUGCUUCUGAGCAGGCUGUAAUCCUGUCCCUGUGAUGGACAGCAAGCCUUUCUGUGACCUCACCUGCUCAGGUCAGGGUGGAUCCCUCCAGAACGUAAGGUAUGGCAAUUGGCCUAAAUCUGCUUCUGAACACUGAAGCUGAGUGCUCCCAUCUUCCUGCCGUCAGUUGCAGAGACUGGAGAAGCUGCAUCUUCUCAGACACCAAAACCACGGGUUCAGUCACCUGUGUGAGGAGCUCAGUGCUGGAAGAUAAAAUACCAGCACCUGUUUGACACAUCGUGCAUCCAUCCAUCCAUCUGUCCAUCCAUCCAUCCAUCCAUCCAUCCAUCUAUCCAUCCCCAUAGUUAACAGGCAUUAAAGUCAAAUGACACCAUCCCUCUGGUUAAGUUUUAGACUUCCCCAGAAUAGAAACAAGGAAGUAAGGGGGUUGUGGUAAACUCAGUUUCUAGACCUAAGAAGAGAUGGCUCCUUCUCCUUAAUAUUUCCACCCUGAGAGAGCCUCUUAUCAUUGAUAAUUUUAAAACAUAAUUUAAAACCCUAGACCUCUCUCUACAACCCUAGUUACUGUUCUCUUUACAUAUAUUCUCCCAUUGCAACCAAAGUUCUAUGAAGAAUUCUCAAUACUCAACUCACAUCCCUUUGCACCUCCCUCCACCUCAGUCCUCAUUCCUCAUCUAAUGGUGCUUUGUUCCCGCACCCCUCUGUUGAAAUGAACCCCAUCAAAACCAACAGCCACCCCUUUGUCCCAUUUAUAGAUCAAGAGUGUUAAAAUGAACAUCUAUAUGGAGACAAAGCUUCCCCCGCAAUGACAAAAUUCAGUUGCUUUUGUAUAGACAAAGAUUAUAUUGCAAUGCUAUAUUUACCUAAAAGCUAGCAUUGUAAAAUAGCUUCCAUAAGAGUCAGUCAGAUAACGUGAAGGCUGUGCUACAGGAACUGUGCUAUCAGUUGAAGUACAACAUUUCCCCAACAUAUCCCAUACUAUUGCUUCAAUAAAAGGAAUUUUGCAAAUAGAUUUACUGCAUGUUAGCAAUAUUUUUAUGAUCACUUCAAUAAAUUCUGUUUAUUGUUUUAUUUCUUUCUGAAGGAAUUACUAAGUAUGCAAUGUAAUCGCCUGAAAUUAAAAUGUUGUUUCAAAAUUUGUCGUGGUUAAAUAUAUUGCCUAAAAGCAUUGUCUGAUUGUUUAAUAUGCCAUAAUUUGGUAAUAUAAUGGUGGUGAAAUAUAAUAGUAGAUAGAGGGAACUCUUGCAGUCUCCUGAUUAGGUCAGAAUUCUUCUACUGCACCACACAAAUCAUAAUUCUGGAAUUCCUUUUGGAAUGUUUCCAUUUGGUAAACUAUCACAACUAUAUGAUAAGUGUACAUGAUUCCAUACUGAUAUAAAUUAAGUGUUUCCAUUGACAAAGAAAUGGGUCAGAGAAGACAAAUUGUCUCAAUCAAAUAAUUCUAAACAAUAUAUGUGGCUAACCCUCAGUUCAUGAGGUGAAGUUUAAUUCUGUCCUCUACCUCCUAAGAACAGGGCUGACUUAGUGACUUACUUCUACAGAAAAGAGUAUAGGAAUGUAAAAUAGUUACCACACACUGGAGAAAUUUGGCAAACAGUACCUUAACCAAGUGAUGAAGGUUAACAUCACCAUUGAUAUCAUAUGGGUAGCAUGUAAACCCAUAUAUGGUGUGAUAAAAAGGGCAAUUCAUCUCUGCGGUAUUCCUUCUGAAAACCCAUAACCUCAGUCUAAUAAUGAGAAAAACAAGUUAUGCCUGUACUUCUCAUGAAAUCAAGCUUAUGAAAAUAGUCUGGCCAUACCUCAAAUGGUUAACAGGGAGUUACCAUAUGACACAGCAAUUCCACCCCUAGGUACAUAGCCAAAAGAAAUAUGCCUACAUAAAAACUUGUACCUGAAUGUAUACAGGAUCAUCAUUCAAAAUAGCCAAAGAGUGGAAACAACCCAAAUGCUCAUCAAUUGAUACAUGGAUAAAAUGUGGUAUAUUCAGCAAUAAAUAUGGAUGAGGAACUGAUAUAUGCUGCAACACAGAUUUUGAAAACAUUAUGUAAAGUGAAAGAAGCCAGAUGCAAAAGACCAAAUAUUGUUUGAUUUCACUUAUAUAAAAUGUCAAAAACAAGCAAAUCCACAGAGAAACAAAGCAUAUCUGUGAUUGCCUAGGGCUGGGGGUGGGCACAGGGAUUAACUGCAUUCAAGCAGGAUGGGUAAUCUUAGGGUGAUGAAAAUGUCUAAAACUCAACGAUGAAGUCCCAGCUACAGCAAUCAGACAAGAGAAAGAAAUAAAGGGCAUCCAAACUGGAAAAGAAGAAGUCAAAUUAUCCUUGUUUGCAGAUGACAUGAUCUUAUAUUUGGAAAAACCUAGACUCCAUCAAAAAACGAUUAGAACUCAUAAACAAAUUCAGUAUAGUUGCAAGAUACAAAAUCAACAUACAAAAAUCAGUAGUGUUUCUAUAUGCCAGCCAAGAGUGAACAAUCUAAAAAAUAAAUUUAAAAGUAAUCCCAUUUACAAUAGCCAUAAAUAAAAUUAAAUACACAGGAAUUAACCAAAGAAGUGAAAGGCCUCUAUAAUGAAAGCUAUAAAACACUGAUGACAGAAAUUGAAGAUGACGCCAAAAAAUGGAAAAGUAUUUCAUGUUCAUUGAUUGGAAGAAUCAAUAUUGUUAAAAUGUCCAUUCUACUCAAAGCAAUCUACAGAUUUAAUACAAUCCCUAUCAAAAUACCAAUGACAUUCUCCACAGAAACAGAACAAUCCUAAAAUUCAUAUAGAAUCACAAAAGACCCAGAAUUCCCAAAGCUAUCUUGAGCAAAAAGAACAAAACUGGAGGAAUCACAAUACCUCACUUCAAAUUAUACUACAGAGCUAUAUCACCAAAACAGCAUGGUACUGGCAUAAAAACAGACACAUAGACCAGUGGAACAGAAUAAAGAACCCAGAAACAAAUCCACACACCUACAGUGAACCCAUUUUCAACAAAGAACCUAUACUGAGGAAAAGACAGUCUCUUCAAUAAGUGGUGCUGGGAAAUCUGGAAAUCCAUACGCAGAAGAAUGAAAAUAGACCCUCUAUUUCUUGCCAUAUACAAAAAUUAAAUCAAUAUCAGUUAAAGGCUUAAAUCUAAGACUUCAAACUAUGAAACUACAAGACUUUGGGGAAACUCUCCAGGACAUUGGUCUGGGCAAAGAUUUCUAGAGUAAUACCCCAACACAGGCAACCAAAGCAAAAACGGACAAAUGGAAUCACAUCAAGUUAAAAAGCUUUUGCACAGCAAAGGAAACAAUCAACAAAGUGAAGAGACAACCCACAGAAUGGGAGAAAAUAUUUGCAGACUACCCAUUUGACAAGGGAUUAAUAACCAGAAUAUAUAAUGAGCUCAAACAACUCUAUAGCAAAAAUAACUAAACUGAUUAAAAGGUGGGCAAAAGAUUUGAAUAGACAUUUCUCUAAAGAAGACAUACAAAUGGCAGACAGGCAUAUGAAAAGGUGCUCAACUUCAUUGAUCAUCAGAGAAAUGCCAAUCCAAACUACAACAAGAUAUCAUCUCACCCCAGUUAAAAUGGCUUAUAUCCAAAAGACAGGCAAUAACAAAUGCUGGCAAGGAUGUGGAGAAAAGGGAAACCUUGUACACUGUUGGUAGGAAUGUAAGUUAGUAAAACCACUAUGUAGAACAUUUUGAAGGUUCCUCAAAAAAACUAAAAAUUGAACUUCCAUAUGACCCGCAAUCCCACUGCUGGGUAUAUACCCAAAAGAAAGGAAAUCAGUAUAUUAAAGAGACAUCUGCACUCCCAUGUUUGUUGCAGCACUGUUCACUAUAGCUAACAUUUGGAAGCAACUUAAGUGUCCAUCAAGAGAUGAAUGGAUAAAGAAAAUGUGGUACACAUACACAACGGAGUACUAGUCAGCCAUCAAGAAGAAUGUGAUUCAGUCAUUUGCAAAAACAUGGAUGGAACUGGAAGUCAUUAUGUUAAGUAAAAUAAGCCAGGCACAGAAAGACAAACAUUGCAUGUUCUCACUUAUUUGUGGGAGAUAAAAAUGAACGCAAUUGAACUCAUGGAGGUAGAGACUAGAAGGAUGGUUACUAGAGGCUGGGAAGGAUGGUGGCAGGCUGGAGGGGAGGUGCAUAUGGUUAAUGAGUAUAAAAAAAUUAGAAAGAAUGAAUAAGACCUAGUACUUGGUAGCACAACAGGGGGACAAUAGUCAAUAAUAAUUUAAGUGUGCAUUUCAAAAUAACUAAAAGAGUAUAAUUGAAUUGUUUGUAACACAAAGGAUAAAUGCUUGAGGGGAUGGAUACCUAAUUUUUAAUGAUGUGAUUAUUACACAUUCCCUACCUGUACCAAAAUCUCAUGUAUCCCCAAAAAUAUAUAUGCCUAUUAUGUACCCACAAAAAUUAAAAAUAAAAGAUUUUAAAACCCUCAA